AGUCGGCCUGCGCUCCUCAGCCUGGCGGUUCUACCUCCGAGGGUUCGCCCGCCCUUGGUUUUCCUUACACCUUAGCCUUUGGCUCCUUUGACCACUCGAAGCCCCACAGCGUGUUCCAGCGGACUUCACCAGCAGACCCAGAAGUGGUGGGUGAAACACUGCCUCUGUUCCUCCUUGAGCCUGUCGGGAGCUGCUGCCUGCCACCACCAUGUCUGCUGCAAAUCCUGAGACUCCAAACUCAACCAUCUCCAGAGAGGCCAGCACCCAGUCUUCAUCAGCUGCAGCUAGCCAAGGCUGGGUGUUACCAGAAGGCAAAAUCGUGCCAAACACUGUUUUUGUUGGUGGAAUUGAUGCUAGGAUGGAUGAAACUGAGAUUGGAAGCUGCUUUGGUAGAUACGGUUCAGUGAAAGAAGUGAAGAUAAUCACGAAUCGAACUGGUGUGUCCAAAGGCUAUGGAUUUGUUUCGUUUGUUAAUGACGUGGAUGUCCAGAAGAUAGUAGGAUCACAGAUACAUUUCCAUGGUAAAAAGCUGAAGCUGGGCCCUGCAAUCAGGAAACAAAAGUUAUGUGCUCGUCAUGUGCAGCCACGUCCUUUGGUAGUUAAUCCUCCUCCUCCACCACAGUUUCAGAACGUCUGGCGGAAUCCAAACACUGAAACCUACCUGCAGCCCCAAAUCACGCCGAAUCCUGUAACUCAGCACGUUCAGUCUGCUGCAAAUCCUGAGACUCCAAACUCAACCAUCUCCAGAGAGGCCAGCACCCAGUCUUCAUCAGCUGCAGCUAGCCAAGGCUGGGUGUUACCAGAAGGCAAAAUCGUGCCAAACACUGUUUUUGUUGGUGGAAUUGAUGCUAGGAUGGAUGAAACUGAGAUUGGAAGCUGCUUUGGUAGAUACGGUUCAGUGAAAGAAGUGAAGAUAAUCACGAAUCGAACUGGUGUGUCCAAAGGCUAUGGAUUUGUUUCGUUUGUUAAUGACGUGGAUGUCCAGAAGAUAGUAGGAUCACAGAUACAUUUCCAUGGUAAAAAGCUGAAGCUGGGCCCUGCAAUCAGGAAACAAAAGUUAUGUGCUCGUCAUGUGCAGCCACGUCCUUUGGUAGUUAAUCCUCCUCCUCCACCACAGUUUCAGAACGUCUGGCGGAAUCCAAACACUGAAACCUACCUGCAGCCCCAAAUCACGCCGAAUCCUGUAACUCAGCACGUUCAGUCUGCUGCAAAUCCUGAGACUCCAAACUCAACCAUCUCCAGAGAGGCCAGCACCCAGUCUUCAUCAGCUGCAGCUAGCCAAGGCUGGGUGUUACCAGAAGGCAAAAUCGUGCCAAACACUGUUUUUGUUGGUGGAAUUGAUGCUAGGAUGGAUGAAACUGAGAUUGGAAGCUGCUUUGGUAGAUACGGUUCAGUGAAAGAAGUGAAGAUAAUCACGAAUCGAACUGGUGUGUCCAAAGGCUAUGGAUUUGUUUCGUUUGUUAAUGACGUGGAUGUCCAGAAGAUAGUAGGAUCACAGAUACAUUUCCAUGGUAAAAAGCUGAAGCUGGGCCCUGCAAUCAGGAAACAAAAGUUAUGUGCUCGUCAUGUGCAGCCACGUCCUUUGGUAGUUAAUCCUCCUCCUCCACCACAGUUUCAGAACGUCUGGCGGAAUCCAAACACUGAAACCUACCUGCAGCCCCAAAUCACGCCGAAUCCUGUAACUCAGCACGUUCAGGCUUACUCUGCUUAUCCACAUUCACCAGGUCAGGUCAUCACUGGAUGUCAGUUGCUUGUAUAUAAUUAUCAGGAAUAUCCUACUUAUCCCGAUUCAGCAUUUCAGGUCACCACUGGAUAUCAGUUGCCUGUAUAUAAUUAUCAGCCAUUUCCUGCUUAUCCAAGAUCACCAUUUCAGGUCACUGCUGGAUAUCAGUUGCCUGUAUAUAAUUAUCAGGCAUUUCCUGCUUAUCCAAAUUCACCAUUUCAAGUCGCCACUGGAUAUCAGUUCCCUGUAUACAAUUAUCAGCCAUUUCCUGCUUAUCCAAGUUCACCAUUUCAGGUCACUGCUGGAUAUCAGUUGCCUGUAUAUAAUUAUCAGGCAUUUCCUGCUUAUCCAAAUUCACCAUUUCAAGUCGCCACUGGAUAUCAGUUCCCUGUAUACAAUUAUCAGGCAUUUCCUGCUUAUCCAAAUUCACCAGUUCAGGUCACCACUGGAUAUCAGUUGCCUGUAUACAAUUAUCAGGCAUUUCCUGCUUAUCCAAGUUCACCAUUUCAGGUCACCACUGGAUAUCAGUUGCCUGUAUAUAAUUAUCAGGCAUUUCCUGCUUAUCCAAAUUCAGCAGUUCAGGUCACCACUGGAUAUCAGUUCCAUGUAUACAAUUACCAGAUGCCACCGCAGUGCCCUGUUGGGGAGCAAAGGAGAAAUCUGUGGACCGAAGCAUACAAAUGGUGGUAUCUUGUCUGUUUAAUCCAGAGAAGAGACUGAUAAAUUCCGUUGUUACUCAAGAUGACUGCUUCAAGGGUAAAAGAGUGCAUCGCUUUAGAAGAAGUUUGGCAGUAUUUAAAUCUGUUGGAUCCUCUCAGCUAUCUAGUUUCAUGGGAAGUUGCUGGUUUUGAAUAUUAAGCUAAAAGUUUUCCACUAUUACAGAAAUUCUGAAUUUUGGUAAAUCACACUGAAACUUUCUGUAUAACUUGUAUUAUUAGACUCUCUAGUUUUAUCUUAACACUGAAACUGUUCUUCAUUAGAUGUUUAUUUAGAACCUGGUUCUGUGUUUAAUAUAUAGUUUAAAGUAACAAAUAAUCGAGACUGAAAGAAUGUUAAGAUUUAUCUGCAAGGAUUUUUAAAAAAUUGAAACUUGCAUUUUAAGUGUUUAAAAGCAAAUACUGACUUUCAAAAAAGUUUUUAAAACCUGAUUUGAAAGCUAACAAUUUUGAUAGUCUGAACACAAGCAUUUCACUUCUCCAAGAAGUACCUGUGAACAGUACAAUAUUUCAGUAUUGAGCUUUGCAUUUAUGAUUUAUCUAGAAAUUUACCUCAAAAGCAGAAUUUUUAAAACUGCAUUUUUAAUCAGUGGAACUCAAUGUAUAGUUAGCUUUAUUGAAGUCUUAUCCAAACCCAGUAAAACAGAUUCUAAGCAAACAGUCCAAUCAGUGAGUCAUAAUGUUUAUUCAAAGUAUUUUAUCUUUUAUCUAGAAUCCACAUAUGUAUGUCCAAUUUGAUUGGGAUAGUAGUUAGGAUAACUAAAAUUCUGGGCCUAAUUUUUUAAAGAAUCCAAGACAAACUAAACUUUACUGGGUAUAUAACCUUCUCAAUGAGUUACCAUUCUUUUUUAUAAAAAAAAUUGUUCCUUGAAAUGCUAAACUUAAUGGCUGUAUGUGAAAUUUGCAAAAUACUGGUAUUAAAGAACGCUGCAGCUUUUUUAUGUCACUCAAAGGUUAAUCGGAGUAUCUGAAAGGAAUUGUUUUUAUAAAAACAUUGAAGUAUUAGUUACUUGCUAUAAAUAGAUUUUUAUUUUUGUUUUUUAGCCUGUUAUAUUUCCUUCUGUAAAAUAAAAUAUGUCCAGAAGAGGCAUGUUGUUUCUAGAUUAGGUAGUGUCCUCAUUUUAUAUUGUGACCACACAGCUAGAGCACCAGAGCCCUUUUGCUAUACUCACAGUCUUGUUUUCCCAGCCUCUUUUACUAGUCUUUCAGGAGGUUUGCUCUUAGAACUGGUGAUGUAAAGAAUGGAAGUAGCUGUAUGAGCAGUUCAAAGGCCAAGCCGUGGAAUGGUAGCAAUGGGAUAUAAUACCUUUCUAAGGGAAACAUUUGUAUCAGUAUCAUUUGAUCUGCCAUGGACAUGUGUUUAAAGUGGCUUUCUGGCCCUUCUUUCAAUGGCUUCUUCCCUAAAACGUGGAGACUCUAAGUUAAUGUCGUUACUAUGGGCCAUAUUACUAAUGCCCACUGGGGUCUAUGAUUUCUCAAAAUUUUCAUUCGGAAUCCGAAGGAUACAGUCUUUAAACUUUAGAAUUCCCAAGAAGGCUUUAUUACACCUCAGAAAUUGAAAGCACCAUGACUUUGUCCAUUAAAAAAUUAUCCAUAGUUUUUUUAGUGCUUUUAACAUUCCGACAUACAUCAUUCUGUGAUUAAAUCUCCAGAUUUCUGUAAAUGAUACCUACAUUCUAAAGAGUUAAUUCUAAUUAUUCCGAUAUGACCUUAAGGAAAAGUAAAGGAAUAAAUUUUUGUCUUUGUUGAAGUAUUUAAUAGAGUAAGGUAAAGAAGAUAUUAAGUCCCUUUCAAAAUGGAAAAUUAAUUCUAAACUGAGAAAAAUGUUCCUACUACCUAUUGCUGAUACUGUCUUUGCAUAAAUGAAUAAAAAUAAACUUUUUUUCUUCAAAUGUG